GGAAGUAGUCCUACAUUCGCGGUCAGCGCGGGGUCUCCGGGCGCCCUGCAGGGCGGGCAGGCUGUGCCAUCCCGCCGGACGUCGGGAUGGUGCAGCUGUACAACCUGCACCCGUUCGGGUCGCAGCAGGUGGUGCCCUGCAAGCUGGAGCCGGACCGGUUCUGUGGCGGGGGGCGUGACGCGCUUUUCGUGGCGGCGGGCUGCAAGGUGGAGGCGUUCGCGGUGGCCGGCCAGGAGCUGUGCCAGCCGCGGUGCGCCUUCUCCACGCUGGGCCGGGUGUUGCGCCUGGCCUACAGCGAGGCUGGAGAUUAUUUGGUAGCAAUUGAAGAGAAAAACAAAGCUACAUUUCUACGUGCUUAUGUGAACUGGAGAAAUAAAAGGACUGAAAACUCUCGUGUGUGUAUCCGAAUGAUUGGGCAUAAUGUGGAGGGACCAUUCAGCAAAGCCUUCAGAGACCAGAUGUACAUUAUUGAAAUGCCGCUUUCGGAGGCCCCCUUGUGCAUUUCCUGUUGCCCUGUGAAAGGAGACCUUCUCGUUGGCUGCACAAAUAAAUUAGUCUUAUUUAGUUUGAAGUACCAGAUCAUUAAUGAGGAAUUCUCACUAUUGGACUUUGAACGUUCUUUAAUUAUACACAUAGAUAAUAUCACUCCUGUUGAGGUUUCUUUUUGUGUUGGAUAUGUUGCUGUCAUGUCAGACUUAGAAGUCUUAAUCGUAAAACUGGAGUCAGGCCCUAAAAAUGGAGAGAGAGUUCACCACCAUCCACAUAAGACCAACAAUCGAAUAAGACGGACAGAAGAAGGCAUCAGUAAUGAAAUUUCACAGCUUGAGUCAGAUGAUUUUGUCAUCUGCCAGAAGCCCCUGGAACUUCUUGGUGAAAAAAGUGAACAGUCUGGAUUAUCUGUUACACUGGAGUCUACGGGAUUAGCUGAUGAAAAAAGAAAAUAUUCCCACUUUCAGCACCUGCUCUAUAGACGUUUUGCUCCUGAUAUUUCGUCCUAUGUCUUGUCUGAUGACAUCAAGCUACAUUCCCUCCAGCUGCUACCCAUUUACCAGACCGGUUCUCUUACAUCUGAUGGAAAAAAUUUGUCUCAGGAAAAAGAAUUGCUGAGUCUCUUUUGCUUUUUCUCCUUACCUCAUGUGGGCUAUCUCUACAUGGUUGUCAAAUCUGUUGAAUUGAUGUCAGUCUACCAGUAUCCUGAAAAGUCUCAGCAGGCAGUACUCACGCCACAAUUUUUGCACGUCAUUACAAGUAACAACCUGCAGUGUUUCACUGUGCGGUGCAGUGCGGCGGCAGCUCGUGAGGAGGACCCGUACAUGGACACCACCCUGAAGGCUUGCCCACCUGUCAGUAUGGAUGUCUGUGCUUUAAGAAUACAGCUUUUCAUAGGCUUGAAAGCCAUCUGUCACUUUAAAAACCACAUCAUACUUUUGACUAAAGCAGAACCUGAAGCCAUUCCAGAGAGAAGACAGUCACCCAAGAGGCUUCUUUCGAGAAAAGAUACCAGUGUUAAAAUCAAAAUACCUCCUGUAGCUGAGGCUGGGUGGAAUUUGUAUAUUGUGAAUACGAUCUCACCAGUGCAGCUGUACAAAGAGAUGGUAGACUAUAGCAAUACCUAUAAGACUGUCAAAACCCAGAGCUGCAUUCACCUUCUCAGUGAGGCUCAUCUGUUAGUGCGAGCUGCCCUGAUGGAUGCCAGUCAGCUGGAACCUGGAGAGAAGGCAGAGCUUUUGGAAGCAUUUAAGGAAAGCUGUGGGCACCUUGGGGACUGUUACAGCAGGCUUGACUCCCAGCAUUCUCAUCUCACCUUGCCAUACUAUAAGAUGUCUGGUUUGUCUAUGGCUGAAGUUCUGGCCCGCACGGACUGGACAGUAGAGGAUGGAUUACAGAAAUACGAGAGAGGAUUAAUCUUUUACAUUAAUCAUUCACUUUAUGAAAACCUGGAUGAAGAAUUAAAUGAAGAAUUAGCAGCAAAAGUGGUUCAGAUGUUUUAUGUGGCUGAGCCAAAGCAAGUGCCCCAUAUUCUCUGUAGUCCUUCUAUGAAGAAUAUUAAUCCUUUAACUGCCAUGAGCUAUCUAAGGAAGCUGGAUACUUCUGGGUUUUCAUCGAUCUUAGUGACAUUGACCAAGGCAGCAGUGGCUCUGAAAAUGGGAGAUCUUGACAUGCACAGAAAUGAAAUGAAAAGCCAUUCAGAGAUGAAGUUGGUAUGUGGCUUCAUUCUGGAACCUCGGCUGUUGAUUCAACAGAGAAAGGGACAGAUUGUUCCAACCGAGCUUGCACUUCACUUGAAGGAAACUCAGCCUGGAUUGCUUGUGGCUUCAGUUCUGGGCUUGCAGAAGAACAACAAAAUUGGAAUUGAAGAAGCAGAUUCCUUUUUUAAGGUGCUUUGUGCUAAGGAUGAAGAUACAAUUCCUCAGCUCUUGGUAGACUUUUGGGAAGCUCAGCUAGUGGCAUGUCUCCCAGAUGUGGUACUUCAGGAACUCUUUUUCAAACUCACAUCACAGUACAUCUGGAGAUUGUCUAAGAGGCAGCCUCCUGACACCACACCAUUGCGAACAUCGGAGGAUCUGAUAAAUGCCUGUAGUCAUUAUGGCUUAAUUUAUCCAUGGGUUCACGUCGUAAUAUCAUCUGAUUCUUUAGCUGAUAAAAAUUAUACAGAAGAUCUUUCAAAAUUACAGUCUCUUAUAUGUGGUCCUUCAUUUGACAUAGCUUCCAUUAUUCCGUUCUUGGAGCCACUUUCAGAAGACACUAUUGCCGGCCUCAGUGUCCAUGUUCUGUGUCGUACACGCUUGAAAGAGUAUGAACAGUGCAUAGACAUACUGUUAGAGAGAUGCCCGGAGGCAGUCAUUCCAUAUGCUAAUCAUGAACUGAAAGAAGAGAACCGGACUCUGUGGUGGAAAAAACUGUUGCCUGAACUUUGUCAGAGAAUAAAAUGUGGUGGAGAGAAGUAUCAACUCUACCUGUCAUCAUUAAAAGAAACAUUGUCAAUUGUUGCUGUGGAACUAGAACUGAAGGAUUUCAUGAAUGUUCUCCCAGAAGAUGGUACUGCAACAUUUUUCUUGCCAUAUCUUCUCUAUUGCAGUCGAAAGAAACCAUUGACUUAAAGGUAUCAUUUGAAAAAUACCAUAAUGGCAUUUGAGACUGAAUUUCUAAAAAUUGAAUGCCAAAGUACAAGUAGAGGAGUUUUUUAUUUUAUAUAUCACACACACACACACACACACACACACACACACACACAUAUAUGAUACAAAUGCUUUCAGGCUGCUUACCUUACCGUGUAGUGGUAACUAUUCACUUCUUAAUUUAUGACCUCAAUCAAUUUAAUUGUCUAGAAUGUAAAAAGUCUUUAAGACAUAAGAAUUCCUCAAAGAAGCCAUACAUUUUUUAAGGUGGGGAUUGACUUUUAUUCCAAGGAACAACAUCAGUUCACUGUUGUUGGAGACAUGACAAUCAUUUUCAUCCCAAGAACACUUUAAGGAAACAUUUUACAAGUAUGCUUGAAAGAAUGUCACUAACUGGUCCAGAAUUUUAUCUUCUUGAUUUUUCCAGAUUUCUCUAUGUUUUUGAGAAAGAUGUUAAUGUUUUGCCAUGGUAAAAGAUUUCAAACCUCAUUUUUUUUGUUCCUUUUCUUGUUACUUUUAAGAAAACUCAUGCUCUGUUUCUCUGAAUCAAAUGAAGUAGAAGUUUACAAAGCUAACUUUCUUCUUGUCUAGCUAUUAACAUGAUUUGUCAAAUGCAUGUUUUUUUCAGCCAAAGCCUUGUUUCCAUUUUUGUUGAUGUGUACUCUUGCUCUUUUAGCUAGAGUGUAUGUGAAAAUAAAGAAAUACAUCAUUGUAUUCACAACCAUGUGUCUUCAUUUAUAACUUUUUGUUUAAAAAAUUUUUAGUUCAAGUUUAGUUCAUUGAUAUUAUCCUCUGAAUGCAGUUAAGGCUGGGCAGAAAUUCUACUCAUGUGACAUCUGCCACAGGUCUAUUUUGAAGCUUUUCUUCUAAUGGCAAUGUUUGUCCUUACCAGGAUUUAAUCUAUAGAAUUGUCUCUCAACUCUGCUUUUCUCCAGUUCCAGAUAACGUCCUUAAGACCAUCUGUUCAGGGGUUCACAAAACUCAAAUUUGUGUCAUUCUAUUUUAUUUAUUUUAUUUUUUAUUUCCUUCCCUCAUACCUUGCCCAUUCCCUCUGAAUAUUAGGUGUGAUGUCAACAGCAUGUUAGAAGGAUCAAUGGGAAGGCAAUGAUUGAAAACAUUUCAAUGAACCUUAAUAGUGUUCCUUUGAGGAGCACCCAGGAGAAUAUCUGGUCAUAGAUCUUUUUUUAAAUGCAGUUUUAUAAAACCCUAACAGCGGUGAUAUCAUUAGACUGUAUGAAUCAGUUUUAUUACCUAGUGUACAAGUGUCAGUCAUGUAUCAUUAUAUAGUCUGUUGAUCUUUCCAUUUGCAAAAAAUUAAUAGUUUUCCCCCACAAAUGUACAAAGUUGUAUGCUUCCAGUCUUCUUUUAAUGUUUAUAGUCAUUCCAAAGUAACAUUCUAUUUUACACUUUCACAUACAUUGUUAUGAAUCAUUGGUUUUUCUCUUUUUUCCACUUAUCACCAAUUUAUUUCAUUCAGCCAGAUUUGGUGUCU